GGAGACCGACUCGGGAUCUGUCCGAGCAGGAAGCCAGCCUCAGCCCGGCCGCUGUCGCCGCCCUGUCCUGGUGCCCGUCCGCGUCGUCGCCCUCUUCACUGGCCCUCAUCACUUCUCACCGCGCCCUCCAGCUUCACCCGUACAGGUAGCCCCGCCGCCGCGCACCUGCCUUCGCUCCCGCACCGGUGACAGUGGAUAGUGGAAACAGGAGAUCGUGGAUCCUCCUUCAAAAAUGGAGGAUGGAAAGCCCGUUUGGGCGCCACACCCUACAGAUGGAUUUCAGAUGGGCAAUAUUGUGGAUAUUGGCCCCGACAGCUUAACAAUUGAACCCUUGAAUCAGAAAGGCAAGACAUUUUUGGCUCUCAUAAACCAAGUGUUUCCUGCAGAAGAGGACAGUAAAAAAGAUGUGGAAGAUAACUGUUCACUAAUGUAUUUAAAUGAAGCCACACUGCUCCAUAAUAUCAAAGUUCGAUAUAGUAAAGACAGAAUUUAUACAUAUGUCGCCAACAUUCUGAUUGCAGUGAAUCCAUACUUUGACAUACCUAAAAUAUAUUCUUCAGAAGCAAUAAAGUCAUAUCAAGGAAAAUCUCUUGGGACAAGACCACCUCAUGUCUUUGCAAUUGCUGAUAAAGCUUUUCGAGACAUGAAGGUGCUCAAGAUGAGUCAGUCUAUCAUUGUAUCUGGAGAAUCAGGAGCCGGCAAAACAGAAAAUACAAAAUUUGUUCUAAGAUACCUGACUGAAUCCUAUGGAACAGGUCAAGAUAUUGAUGACAGAAUUGUUGAAGCUAACCCACUCCUAGAAGCCUUUGGAAAUGCGAAGACUGUUCGCAACAAUAAUAGCAGUCGAUUUGGGAAAUUUGUAGAAAUACAUUUUAAUGAAAAGAGCUCAGUUGUUGGAGGAUUUGUUUCACAUUAUCUCCUAGAGAAAUCUAGGAUCUGUGUUCAAGGCAAAGAGGAAAGAAAUUAUCAUAUCUUUUAUAGGUUGUGUGCUGGUGCUUCUGAAGAUAUUAGAGAAAAACUUCAUUUGAGUUCACCAGAUAAUUUUCGGUAUUUAAACCGAGGCUGCACUAGAUACUUUGCUAACAAAGAAACUGACAAACAGAUUUUACAGAACCGCAAAAGUCCUGAGUACCUUAAGGCAGGUUCUAUGAAAGAUCCUCUGCUAGAUGACCAUGGUGAUUUUAUUAGAAUGUGCACGGCUAUGAAAAAAAUUGGUUUGGAUGAUGAAGAAAAGCUUGAUCUCUUCCGGGUAGUAGCUGGCGUCCUGCACCUUGGAAAUAUUGAUUUUGAGGAAGCUGGCAGCACUUCAGGUGGUUGUAAUCUGAAGAAUAAAUCUGCUCAGUCUUUGGAAUAUUGUGCUGAAUUACUGGGUUUGGACCAAGAUGAUCUUCGAGUAAGUUUGACCACAAGAGUCAUGCUAACAACAGCAGGGGGCACCAAAGGAACAGUUAUAAAGGUACCUCUGAAAGUGGAGCAAGCAAACAAUGCUCGUGAUGCCCUGGCAAAGACAGUGUAUAGCCAUCUUUUUGAUCAUGUGGUAAACAGAGUAAAUCAGUGUUUUCCUUUUGAAACAUCAUCCUAUUUUAUUGGAGUCCUAGAUAUUGCUGGUUUUGAGUACUUUGAGCAUAACAGUUUUGAACAAUUUUGCAUCAACUAUUGCAAUGAAAAACUUCAACAAUUUUUUAAUGAAAGGAUUCUGAAGGAGGAACAAGAACUCUAUCAAAAAGAAGGUUUAGGUGUUAAUGAAGUGCAUUAUGUGGAUAAUCAGGACUGUAUAGAUUUAAUUGAAGCCAAAUUAGUGGGAAUACUGGAUAUUUUGGAUGAAGAAAAUCGCCUUCCCCAGCCAAGUGAUCAACACUUUACAUCUGCAGUUCACCAAAAGCACAAGGAUCAUUUUCGACUCACUAUUCCCAGAAAAUCUAAGCUGGCAGUUCAUAGGAAUAUCAGAGACGACGAAGGCUUCAUUAUCAGGCAUUUUGCGGGGGCAGUGUGCUAUGAAACAACCCAGUUUGUGGAGAAAAAUAAUGAUGCUUUACAUAUGUCUCUUGAAUCCUUAAUAUGUGAAUCCAGAGAUAAGUUUAUACGGGAAUUAUUUGAAUCAUCCACAAAUAACAACAAAGAUACUAAACAAAAAGCAGGAAAACUUAGCUUCAUCAGCGUGGGAAACAAGUUUAAGACACAGUUAAAUUUGCUUCUGGAUAAACUUCGAAGUACUGGAGCAAGCUUUAUUCGUUGCAUCAAACCUAACUUAAAGAUGACAAGCCACCACUUUGAAGGUGCUCAAAUUCUGUCUCAGCUUCAGUGUUCAGGGAUGGUGUCUGUUUUGGACUUGAUGCAGGGUGGUUACCCAUCACGAGCUUCAUUUCAUGAACUCUACAACAUGUACAAAAAGUAUAUGCCAGAUAAACUUGCAAGAUUGGAUCCAAGACUAUUUUGUAAGGCUUUGUUUAAAGCUUUGGGCUUAAAUGAAAAUGACUACAAGUUUGGGUUAACCAAAGUAUUUUUUAGACCUGGCAAGUUUGCAGAAUUUGAUCAGAUCAUGAAGUCUGACCCUGACCACUUAGCAGAGUUGGUUAAAAGAGUCAAUCACUGGCUCACAUGCAGUCGCUGGAAGAAAGUUCAGUGGUGCUCACUCUCAGUCAUCAAAUUGAAAAACAAAAUAAAAUAUCGAGCUGAAGCCUGCAUUAAAAUGCAAAAAACUAUUCGAAUGUGGCUUUGCAAGAGGAGACACAAACCUCGCAUUGAUGGUCUGGUUAAGGUGGGCACACUGAAAAAACGACUUGAUAAAUUUAAUGAGGUAGUCAGUGUGUUGAAAGAUGGAAAACCCGAGAUGAAUAAACAGAUCAAGAAUCUGGAAAUUUCUAUUGAUACUUUGAUGGCCAAAAUUAAGUCCACUAUGAUGACGCAGGAACAAAUCCAGAAAGAAUAUGAUGCACUGGUUAAAAGCUCAGAGGAACUCCUCAGUGCAUUACAGAAAAAAAAACAGCAGGAAGAGGAAGCAGAAAGGCUGAGGCGUAUUCAAGAAGAAAUGGAAAAGGAAAGAAAAAGACGUGAAGAAGACGAAAAACGUCGAAGAAAGGAAGAGGAGGAAAGGCGGAUGAAACUUGAGAUGGAAGCAAAGAGAAAACAAGAAGAAGAAGAGAGAAAGAAAAGGGAAGAUGAUGAAAAACGCAUUCAAGCUGAAGUGGAGGCACAGCUGGCCCGACAGAAGGAGGAGGAAUCCCAACAGCAAGCAGUUCUGGAGCAGGAGCGCAGGGACCGGGAGCUGGCCCUGAGGAUUGCCCAGAGUGAAGCCGAGCUCAUCAGUGAUGAGGCCCAGGCCGACCUGGCGCUGCGGAGCUUGGAUUCCUAUCCGGUAACUUCUAAAAAUGAUGGAACAAGACCCAAAAUGACACCGGAACAAAUGGCCAAAGAAAUGUCAGAAUUUUUGAGUAGAGGUCCUGCUGUACUAGCCACCAAAGCAGCUGCUGGUACUAAGAAAUAUGAUCUUAGUAAAUGGAAAUAUGCAGAACUACGUGAUACCAUCAAUACUUCUUGUGAUAUUGAGCUCCUGGCAGCUUGCAGAGAAGAAUUUCAUAGGAGACUAAAAGUGUAUCAUGCUUGGAAAUCUAAGAACAAGAAGAGAAAUACUGAAACAGAGCAACGUGCUCCAAAGUCUGUUACUGAUUAUGAUUUUGCACCAUUUUUGAACAAUUCACCUCAGCAAAACCCAGCAGCUCAGAUUCCUGCCAGGCAGCGGGAGAUUGAAAUGAACCGACAGCAACGCUUCUUCCGCAUCCCAUUCAUCCGCCCUGCCGACCAGUACAAAGACCCUCAGAGUAAGAAAAAAGGCUGGUGGUAUGCCCAUUUUGAUGGACCAUGGAUUGCCCGGCAAAUGGAACUCCAUCCUGACAAGCCACCCAUCCUACUUGUGGCUGGUAAGGACGACAUGGAGAUGUGUGAGCUGAAUCUUGAGGAGACUGGCCUGACUCGGAAGCGUGGUGCUGAGAUCUUGCCAAGACAGUUUGAAGAAAUCUGGGAACGCUGUGGAGGCAUCCAGUACCUUCAGAAUGCGAUUGAGAGCAGACAGGCUCGGCCCACCUAUGCAACAGCCAUGCUGCAGAGUCUGUUAAAGUAGAUGUUGCACACCAGCCUUACAGCUGGGAGCCUUUGCCAUGGUACUUAGGUAGGGUGUGUGCCCCCAGAUUUAACCAUUCCAUAAUCAUGUUAGAGUUACUUCUAUAAAGUGAACAGAUUUUAUUAAUCACGGCUUUUGGUGAAUUUGUUUAAGGUUAAUUAUGGUAGCAAAUUUUGGACCUAAACAUUAUUUUUCUGUAUCCCGCUGUAAUUCCCAAAACUCUCAUUAUUCUCUAACUAUUACACAUGGGCAUAUUCUGAUGUUUCUCAUCCUUUGCCAGAAGACUACCUUACAUCCAUCGUAAUUGUUCUCUAGGAAAAGAGAACUUUUUUCAAAAUUCAAAAUACUUUUUAAGGAUGGCACAGUACCAUAUAACUGGAGUAAUAAAACAUGAGCUUACAUUCUUACAAUAACUAAACCACUUAAAAUGAUCAAGGCACUAAUGUUUUGGUCUGAAAAGCUGUGUACUUUAUAGACAUUUUCAGACAUUUUUGGAAAUUUCCAUUAAAGGUGGAAAAUCUAUUUUUUUCCUCCUUUGCAGUGUCUUAGUUUGAAUGAAACACUUCGAAGUUCUAGAAUUCUAGAAAGAGCCUUAAUGUAUUUGAUGUAUUCUGUGAUAAGAGGUACUAAUAGUAUCCAGCACAGAUUUGCUUUUCUUUGCUAGCACAAUGUGUGUUGCUGUCAGAAUAUUCUUUUUAUAUUCUGUGGAAAAAUAAAGGAAAUUCAGAUUGUUUAAAUGCCUAAAAGUUUUGAGAUAAGUUUUGUUUCAAUUAGAAAAGGAAAUAGGUUUUAGGUGGCAUAGUGGCUUAACUGGACUGAAUUCAAAUAUUCUUUCAACUUCAUCUCAAUAGUGAUUUUUGUAUCAGAAUCUUGUCCAAGUUGUUUCAUUGAUUUAGUAAGUGUUCUGCUUCCAACAUCUUUCUUUUUAAGAAAUUCCUAGUGUCUUUUUUGGCCUUUGAGGUUUUGGUAAUUGUAGACCUGUUUCAUAAGCUUUGUAAUUCAGAAAUCCUUGUAUUUAGUAAGUGCUUGUUUUACAUAACUGAUAAUUUUAAAAUGUUUUCUUUGUGUGCUGUUAGUAUUGAUUCAAAUGUCAGCAGCUUUAAGCCUAAUAUUUAUGACUUUCACAUUUGGAAUUUAAAGACAAAAAUACAUCAAGGAGUUAUGCUGACAUAAUUCUAAGGAGUUUUGUUGUAUUUUAGAAUAAAAUUAUAAAGUAAAAUGAUUCUCUGUACUGCUUUUUCCCCCAGUUUUUAGAGACCCUAACCUUUGAAAUGAAAUUCCAGUGAUUUCUUUUUUCCCUAGAAAGAUUACCUCAGUUAGGGAAGUAUUUCCCAGCUGACUAGUGUUUGUGAGCCACAGACACUGUCUUCAGAAUUGCUUCUCUCAUGUCUUAGUAGAGAAAUAUUUAUUUAUUAUGAUACAUUCAAAUGAUUGUCAAGUUAAAUUAAAUGGUUGUGUCUGUGCUAUUGAGAAUGCAAAUGUGAUUAUCUUUUGAAGGCUGUAUUACUGCAUAGCUUCACCCACCCUCGGGUCAUUUCGUCCCUGUGAUUGGGGACAGAAGGUGUAGCUACUGAAGUAAAUGACCUAUUCUCUCUCUUCCAUCUCUCGCCUUUAACUGGUGUUUUUAUUUGUGUAGGAUAGUGAAUGAUAAGCUUUUUUCCUAACCAGUAGUGAGUAAAGUUCUUGAACAAAAUUUAGUAGCCAAAUUGUUUUUUAAUGACAUGUCUCUUUAGUACAAUAGUUUUGUGUAUCUUUUAGAUACAUUAAUAGGCACUAGAUGGAAAAUUAAAGAGUUAAACAUAUUUAAAUGAGAGAAUCUAAUGUUUCAGAAAUUUGUAAGAAAUGUAUCACAGCAAAGGGUUGUUAUAAGUCCUUAGUUUUUGACUCUAAUAGUUAAUACAAUUAUAGUUAAUCUUAAGCCAUAAUGUUUCUAAUCAUGUCACACAGCUGUCCUAGAACUUAUCUAUUUAAAAUAGUUUCCUGAGUUAAUUUUGGCCAGCAGGGCAACUGCCCUAAUUCAGAUAGAUUUACAGUAACCUACGUACAGUAGAUGCACAUACACACAGACACCCCUUUGCUGGAGAAACUUAGGACCCUGUCAGCCUUUUAAAGGAAACAGCAGGAGUGGUGUCCUAAAUGAUGUUCAUGCAGCUGCUUUACCAUGUUCACAGUCAAGCCCAUGCAUGCCAGGUUAAAACUGUGGAAAUCAAAAGUAAAUUCACUCAUAUUUUAAUCAUUUUAACUGAGAUUUAAAAUUAGAAGUUUAAACCACUAUAUAUAAAGAACUAAUCUUUUCUUAAUACCAGUUCUUUCCAUAGCAUAUGCUUUGCAAAGGCAGCAUGCAUAAAAUAUUUAAAAUGAGAGGACAGAAUGUUUUCACAUUUGAUUCAAUUUUAAUAUAAUUCCUAAUUGUGGUAACACAGUUGAGAUAUGUAUUAUGAGUUAUGGGAACUAAUUGAGAAAAGGAAGUUACUCUAAUCCACGUAUGUUAAGAGAAUAUUGAGUUUUCUUAGUUGUAAAGUUGGGGAGAUGGCACCUUCUCAGAGGAUUGUGAAAAUAUGAGGAAGAAACAAAACAGUGCAUGUAGGAGCACAGGGCCACACAAAGGCAUUCUAUUGUUAUGCUCAUUCUGCUUCUGUAAUGACUUUUCAUAGGUCAUUCUUGUGAACCAUUUUGUUUUGCAAGCAACCAAGGAAAGAACAUCUUAAGUGGAAAAUCAGUGGUGGUUGUGAACACUUAGAGAAUAGCAAUCCACAGGCAAGAAUAAUGGUAUUGUUUGUAGAGCUUUAUUAAUUGGAUAUUUUUUAAAAGACAUUUUCAUUCACAGGUCAUUACUAUGGUUCUCAGCGAUCCAAAUAUGUAGAUCAUUGGUUUUUUUUUUUACCUGAAGUAGCUUAAGAGUACUUGGAUCAGUAGAAUAAAUAUUUAUUGAAUCAAUCAGUCAGCCAAUUAAUAUGAUGUUAGUGAUAGACCUGCCUCCUUUUAUGGAAGAGGUAACAGAUCCAGAGAGGUCAAGUAAUUUAGUUGUAGACUGAAAAAUAUAUCAAAGCCUUUGCUGCAAUCAUAUGUAACAAAAAGAACCAAAACAAACACUUUUUAGUGGCACCUGUGGAUUUACAAAGGGUUGCCUCUCUGUCAUUCCACAACUUCAGAAGGUGUGACAGGUUUUCCCUAUUUAUCAUUACCAAUAAUAACAAGUAUUGAGAGUUUUAAAAUUUCUCCCAGAAGAUAAACUAACAAGGAUGGAAGGGGAGGGCAAAGGAUAUCUAAACAUGAGAAUAAGGACAUGUUAGAGGGGGGGAAACAGUUGUAACAAUAAGGAAAGAGAAGAGCAACAGUGGAAGAGACAGGUUGUGUGCCCCUAAAGAUUCUGCACCCCCAGUUUGGAAACACUGAUACAUUUUAGGACACAGAGCACUCCUAGAUCUCUACGAAAUUUUAGAAUGAAUAAUGUGUAAUUUAUAGGAUCAGAACGUAUGGUUAUUAAAACUUGGAUCAAGAUAUGCCCGGUGUAUACAUUCUUAGCACAUAGGAAUGGCACUGCCAUACUGGAGAAGGUCAGCAGUAAAUAGGCAUUCUGUACAUAAGCCUCAUGGAAGGGUAAGAUGGAGAGACUGGCAGAAGUAGCACCUACUCUGCUGGGAGCACUUCUCUGAGUACGCUUUAGUUCAAUUCAAAUCACUGUAUUCUUUCCCCAUUGCUAACCUAAUAUAUGAAACAAGCUUAGCUGUCUCAGAAGUUUUUCAAGAGAUGAUCAGGAAAAAUUAAUGCACAUUCAAAAGGAGAAUCUUCAGUACAAAUUUGUUUUUUUAAAAAUAGAUUUAGGGCUGGGCGCGGUGGCUCACGCCUGUAAUCCCAGCACUUUGGGAGGCCGAGGCGGGUGGAUCACGAGGUCAAGACUUCGAGACCAGCCUGGCCAACAUGGUGAAACCCUGUCUCUACUAAAAAUACAAAACAUUAGCCAGGCGUGGUAGUGGGUGCCUGUAAUCCCUGCUACUUGGGAGGCUGAGGCAGGAGAAUCACUUGAACGCGGGAGGCAGAGGUUGCAGGGAGCCGAGAUGGCGCCAUUGCACUCCAUCCUGGGCAACAAGAGCGAAAUUCCAUCUCAAAAAAUAAAAUAGAUUUAGGGGGUACAAGUGCAGUUUUGUUACAUGGGUAUAUUGCAUAGUGGUAAAAUGUGGGCUUUUAGUGUACCUAACACCCAGAGAAGCAUACAUUGUGCCCAGUAGGUAAUUUUUCAUCCCUAAACCUUUUCUCAGCCUCCCACUUUCUGGAGUCUCCAAUGUCGGUUAUUCCACUCUUUAUGUCCAUAUCUACACAUUCAAUCCUAAUUUGUACCAAGUAGCAUCUCACCUUUAAAUCACAGGCUUAUUAGUUGGGUGUUUUCUUUUUACUUAUGAAAAUUCAUCUAGUCAAACUGUCAAUUAAUUUUUCCUCAUUUCAUUAAAAGUGUAUAUCUAAUGCUUUCUCUAAAAAUUGAUGUACUGGAAAUACAAAUAAAUAAAUGCUCCCUGUGUAGAAUUUC